ACAGCAGUCCGUGCCGCCGUCCCGCCCGCCAGCGCCCCAGCGAGGAAGCAGCGCGCAGCCCGCGGCCCAGCGCACCCGCAGCAGCGCCCGCAGCUCGUCCGCGCCAUGUUCCAGGCGGCCGAGCGCCCCCAGGAGUGGGCCAUGGAGGGCCCCCGCGACGGGCUGAAGAAGGAGCGGCUACUGGACGACCGCCACGACAGCGGCCUGGACUCCAUGAAAGACGAGGAGUACGAGCAGAUGGUCAAGGAGCUGCAGGAGAUCCGCCUCGAGCCGCAGGAGGUGCCGCGCGGCUCGGAGCCCUGGAAGCAGCAGCUCACCGAGGACGGGGACUCGUUCCUGCACUUGGCCAUCAUCCAUGAAGAAAAGGCACUGACCAUGGAAGUGAUCCGCCAGGUGAAGGGAGACCUGGCCUUCCUCAACUUCCAGAACAACCUGCAGCAGACUCCACUCCACUUGGCUGUGAUCACCAACCAGCCAGAAAUUGCUGAGGCACUUCUGGGAGCUGGCUGUGAUCCUGAGCUCCGAGACUUUCGAGGAAAUACCCCCCUACACCUUGCCUGUGAGCAGGGCUGCCUGGCCAGCGUGGGAGUCCUGACUCAGUCCUGCACCACCCCGCACCUCCACUCCAUCCUGAAGGCUACCAACUACAAUGGCCACACGUGUCUACACUUAGCCUCUAUCCAUGGCUACCUGGGCAUCGUGGAGCUUUUGGUGUCCUUGGGUGCUGAUGUCAAUGCUCAGGAGCCCUGUAAUGGCCGGACUGCCCUUCACCUCGCAGUGGACCUGCAAAAUCCUGACCUGGUGUCACUCCUGUUGAAGUGUGGGGCUGAUGUCAACAGAGUUACCUACCAGGGCUAUUCUCCCUACCAGCUCACCUGGGGCCGCCCAAGCACCCGGAUACAGCAGCAGCUGGGCCAGCUGACACUAGAAAACCUUCAGAUGCUGCCAGAGAGUGAGGAUGAGGAGAGCUAUGACACAGAGUCAGAGUUCACGGAGUUCACAGAGGACGAGCUGCCCUAUGAUGACUGUGUGUUUGGAGGCCAGCGUCUGACGUUAUGAGCGCAAAGGGGCUGAAAGAACAUGGACUUGUAUAUUUGUACAAAAAAAAAGUUUUAUUUUUCUAAAAAAAGAAAAAAGAAGAAAAAAUUUAAAGGGUGUACUUAUAUCCACACUGCACACUGCCUGGCCCAAAACGUCUUAUUGUGGUAGGAUCAGCCCUCAUUUUGUUGCUUUUGUGAACUUUUUGUAGGGGACGAGAAAGAUCAUUGAAAUUCUGAGAAAACUUCUUUUAAACCUCACCUUUGUGGGGUUUUUGGAGAAGGUUAUCAAAAAUUUCAUGGAAGGACCACAUUUUAUAUUUAUUGUGCUUCGAGUGACUGACCCCAGUGGUAUCCUGUGACAUGUAACAGCCAGGAGUGUUAAGCGUUCAGUGAUGUGGGGUGAAAAGUUACUACCUGUCAAGGUUUGUGUUACCCUCCUGUAAAUGGUGUACAUAAUGUAUUGUUGGUAAUUAUUUUGGUACUUUUAUGAUGUAUAUUUAUUAAACAGAUUUUUACAAA